AGAAGUUUUCUGACUCCUUUCGGAGGAGCCUCCGGGACCCCGGGGAGUAACAGGUGUCUGGAGGCUGAAGGGUGGAGGGGUUCCUGGAUUUGGGGUUUGCUUGUGAAACUCCCCUCCACCCUCCUCUCUCGCACCCACCCACCCCCUCACCCCCUUCUUUUUCCGUCCUUGGAAAAUGGUGUCCAAGCUCACGUCGCUCCAGCAAGAACUCCUGAGCGCCCUGCUGAGCUCCGGGGUCACCAAGGAGGUGCUGGUUCAGGCCUUGGAGGAGUUGCUGCCAUCCCCGAACUUCGGGGUGAAGCUGGAGACGCUGCCCCUGUCCCCUGGCAGCGGGGCCGAGCCCGACACCAAGCCGGUCUUCCAUACUCUCACCAACGGCCACGCCAAGGGCCGCUUGUCCGGCGACGAGGGCUCCGAGGACGGCGACGACUAUGACACACCUCCCAUCCUCAAGGAGCUGCAGGCGCUCAACACCGAGGAGGCGGCGGAGCAGCGGGCGGAGGUGGACCGGAUGCUCAGUGAGGACCCUUGGAGGGCUGCUAAAAUGAUCAAGGGUUACAUGCAGCAACACAACAUCCCCCAGAGGGAGGUGGUCGAUGUCACCGGCCUGAACCAGUCGCACCUCUCCCAGCAUCUCAACAAGGGCACCCCUAUGAAGACCCAGAAGCGUGCCGCUCUGUACACCUGGUACGUCAGAAAGCAACGAGAGAUCCUCCGACAAUUCAACCAGACAGUCCAGAGUUCUGGAAAUAUGACAGACAAAAGCAGUCAGGAUCAGCUGCUGUUUCUCUUUCCAGAGUUCAGUCAACAGAGCCAUGGGCCUGGGCAGUCCGAUGAUGCCUGCUCUGAGCCCACCAACAAGAAGAUGCGCCGCAACCGGUUCAAAUGGGGGCCCGCGUCCCAGCAAAUCUUGUACCAGGCCUACGAUCGGCAAAAGAACCCCAGCAAGGAAGAGAGAGAGGCCUUAGUGGAGGAAUGCAACAGGGCAGAAUGUUUGCAGCGAGGGGUGUCCCCCUCCAAAGCCCACGGCCUGGGCUCCAACUUGGUCACUGAGGUCCGUGUCUACAACUGGUUUGCAAACCGCAGGAAGGAGGAGGCAUUCCGGCAAAAGCUGGCCAUGGACGCCUAUAGCUCCAACCAGACUCACAGCCUGAACCCUCUGCUCUCCCACGGCUCCCCCCACCACCAGCCCAGCUCCUCUCCUCCAAACAAGCUGUCAGGUGUUUUAUGGAUGGAGACAGAAAUGAGCGGCCGUUCUUCUUCAUUGUCUACAACCCUACAGCCAGGGGAACUAGAGGGUUUGCAUCCCUACCUGUAAACUUCAAUCUCACCGUGAAGAAGAAGGUCCCCGAAGUCUCUGAACACCUUGCUCUGUAUGUAUGUAUUCUGAGUGGCAGAAUUGUGGGCUGUACCAACAUCUGAGCCUGAGGUAGCUUUCUUCAUCAUUGUGUCUCCAGCCCAUAGCCCUGUGCCUGGCACAUGGUAGACACUCCAUAUAUUUGUGAAAUAAAGAUAUCUAUUAUAGAAGGCUUCCUGUCAAAGCAUAUGCAGAAACCCCCUGUUUUAUAAAUUUGGUAUUCAGUUUAAGAAUUAAACUGAGCCUAGGAUUAGUUUUGUUUUAUAUAGCAUAUAUGUGCUAUAUAAUUAUAUAUAUAUGUAUAUAUAAAGGCAUAUUUUCUCUUCUCUAGAAACAGUGUCACCCAGCUUCAACCCUAUUAACACUGCUUAAGUGUACAGUUCACAAAUUAAUGUCGACAUUUAAUGUUACCAGAAAGUUUUCAAAGAACGUAUCAUGAGUUUCUCCCUAAUGUUCUACUAGUAAACUAGUCUACUCAUUUAAUUUAGUUCUACUAGUUACUUUAAUGUUCUACUACUUUCAUUCAUUUUAAAAUCUCUUACCAGGAUCCCUAGGGCAAGAAAAGAGCAAGAACGUCUCCUCUUUUGUUUCCUUUGAGCAAAAUGAGGUCUAGAAAAGGGACUGGACUACUGCAAAUCAAUUAUCUGGACAGACAGAAACAAAACUGCCCUGCUCUGGGCAGCCAUUAGGUCUCUGGUGGUGCUCCCUGAGCACUUGGCUGGUGCUCCUAUCUCAGUGCCCAACACCUGGUGUUGCUUGGGACGAGCCUCCUUGGGCCUGCCGGUGAUCGGCAGCUAUCUGUCAUGAUGAUGGUGAUGAUGAUGGUGAUAAUGAUACUGAUGGAGAUGCCCUCUGUGACAGUGAUGAAGAGGCUGGGAUCUGGCCAGGCAAAUCCCUAUCACAAGGCAGCUCUGACACUUGCCAGACCUCAAAGGAUCUUCUCCCUGGGUAUCAUCUCCCAGUACGGUCUUUGUUAUGAAUAGGCUGUGGUGGAAAACCUCUCUUUUCUAAGGCAAUUUUAUUAGCCCUUCAGUCACAAUACAGAUGUCUGUUUAUAGGACCUUACUUUUGUGUGGACACCCAGUGGCUCAGUCUGCUGAUGGCUUUAUAGCCUUUCUCCCUUUGCCCAGACCCACUGGGAGCAUCACCAUUCUCCUUGUCCACUAGGCCUAGAGGCCUUUGUUGCAGCCAUAUUAUCUCUGCCUGCAAAGGCAGCUGCUCAGAAAAUACCAGACCCCGGGAGCCAGACUGCAGAAGGGCACUCUGUGUCCCCACAGCCUUUAGGCCUAACGAUGUCCACCAUUAACCCUUCUUAGUUUUACUCUAGUUUCUUUGGAGAAAGGGGCAUUUAAAAGUUAUUCAUGUUGCCACAGUAAAUUCCCAUUAAUUGACUCUUCUCCUUAUCCCCAAAUCAACCCAGUAGCCCCCAAACUCGGUUCUUCAAAUGUGAAACUGCCCAAGUCUAUCAAUACUGUUUCUUCAAUUUUGAUUGUAUUUUAAUCUCUCUCUCCUCUUCUCUUACUCCUCUUUCUUCCUCCUUAAAAAGAAUGCUUGCCUCUCCUUGCCCAUGGAAAAACAGGGAGGGGAGGCCAAAGCAGAAGGACUACUUGAGCCCAGGAGUUUGAGACUACCCUGGGCAACAUAGACCCCCCCAUCUCUUCAAAAUAAUAAUAACAAUAAUAAUAAUAAUAUUAAUAAAUUAGCCAGGCAUGGUGGCAUGUGCCUGUAGUCUCAACUAUUUUUGGGGGCUGAGGUGGGAGGAUUCCUUGAGCCCAGGAGUUCAAGGCUGCAGUGAGCUGUGAUUGCACCACCACAGUCCAGCCUGGGUGACAGAGCUAGAGCUUGCCUCAAAAAAGAAAAGAAAAACUGGGAGAUUUAGAGGAUAAAUGGACAUACUCCAGUCACUUCACCACCACUCAACUCAACAGUCUAAAGGUGAAAGUGAUGUGGAGUCAUCAGUCAGAGUUUAAGCAUAGGUUAUUCAUUCAUCAUUUACUCCUUCAAUAAAUGUUUACUGAAUGCUUAGCAUGACUCUGCCAAGAAGAAAAUGGAGAAUACAGACAAGGUCCUGCCCUCAUGGGGCUUACAUUACAGUGAGGGAUGCAGCCAAGGAACAAGUAAACAAACCUGCAAGAUCAUUUCAAGCUAUUAGUGGGUCGUGAUGGGGAGGCUCUACAUAUCUGGAGCCCAUUUGGGGCUUAGGAGGAAGAGGGAGAAGGGUCAGCUUUGGAAUACCACGGACUUGCUGGGAGACCCCCUAGCAAGGAGCGGUGCAAACAACCUUGUCCUCUCCGAACCUCAGUUUUCCACUCUGUCAAAUGGGUGCUUGUGACACAUUGAGAAGCAGAUGGGUGUAACAUACUCUCAGAUGUGAGGACUGCCCAAGUUAUCAAGUGCCAGGCUGGUUCCUUUUACCUACAGCAGCAAUCUUCAGGCUGAAGUAUUCAUUGCAAACUGCCUGAUGUUUGCCUGCAGAAACUGCCACUCUAGUAAGGAUGAGGCGUGGUGGCCCAGGUAGACCUUGUGGGGGAGGACACACAGAGUUUCUGUUGGUCUUCUACCUCCCCACAUGUGCAAUUUUUUCAAGUGCACCAUGCAUGUUAGCUUCUGUUCUCAGCCAAGGUGCUUUUGAUGAAAGAUUUUUUUUUCUUUUCUUGGUUACAUUUGCUUUGAUUUUUUUUUUAAAUAAGAAAACCAGUUUGUGGGCUUCCCUUAAGUAUCACUCAACUUUUACUCCUUGAGUCAAGAAUGUUUACUGUCCCUGCAGGCCUGUCUGUAUUUCUCCUCUUAUGAAUUGAGCUCCUAACUAAGCCAUGUUAGGUAGAAAGGGAUCCGGAAUUGAAACCAGCCCAGCAUUUAAAUUGCUUUCAUCUUGCAUCAGCUUUUUCUUCCACAUUUGCAGAUUUUUAAUCUUCUAAACUCUUUGCAAACAUGAAUCUUUAUCCUCUCAGAGGAGGAAAUAUUAAUAAGAACUAGCAAAAGUCCAGUGCUACAAACAAGGAAACUGAGGCAGCAAUGCUAACUCAUUCGAAAGCUUUCAUUUCUGGAGUUCUCAAUUUCAAGCCAGGGAAUUGUUCACAUUCUUUUCUUCCAAAUGGGCCUCUCAGAAGUUCACCAGACAGAAUCAUUUGUCUCUCUGCCUCUGUCCUUAAGAAAAGUAAAGUGUUUAGGGAGAAGGUAGAGUUAUCAGGACACAGUACUGGGUCCAUCAAGCCUGGCCCAGUCUCUCCCUGUCAUCUCCCCAACAUAAUGAUUUGGCUUCAUAGAAAAGAUGGCUGUGUCUACUCAUAAUUUAUGAACAAUGAACAUAGUUAUUACCUUUUGGAAGAGCUUUCUCCUUCGCAUGCUCUCUCCUGCCUGAGUUUAAAUUCCCAGUUUCUAGACCCAACAGGGCUGGGCUGCACUCUGCAUGAGGUUAGAAACACAGGGGAAGAAUGUGUGUGACAGAGCCCCAGCCAGUUGAGUAAUGUUUACUCUGUUGGUGGCUGGGACGCUCACUUACGCUGGCAGAGGUCCACCAGCCGGAGGAACAUUCCUGCAUUAUCAGGGAUGGGAGGUUGGCUCUGAAAUGUCAAGGGUGAAAGGCAUCCCACCAGAUUCUGGGUGCAGCUCAUAGACUUCAGUGAAAGGAACCCCCAGGUUUCAGUGCCAAAAGCCACAUCGUGGGCAAGCUGAGCCCCACAUUGCCCAGGAAUCCCCACUUCCCUCAUUUCUUCUUACUAAAAGAACAAUUCUGGUCCUGUUUUCUUUGUUGACAUUGCUCUUCUGUUUACCCAGCAGAACCAGUGCAUCUCUGACAUUAUUUUAUUCAUUCAUUAUUCUGGCUUGUGAAGAAGGAAUAUCUGUGUGCCCCUUUCACAGACAAAAAUGCCAAGGCUCAAAAGUUAACUGACCCAGAAUCAUCAGAGAGUUAUGGCAGAGAGAGAGAGAGAGAGAGAGAGAGAGAGAGAGAUUGUUAAAGUGUCUAGAGGCUGGUGCCCAGUUGAUCUCUGGAAUCAUGGAAUUCCAUGAUUUUUUGAAGCUCUUAGAGCUGAAUUAAAUCGCCAGGGGCUCUAUGAGCUGUAGCUCUAAGGCCCUGAAGCACAGGUUUCUGCAAAGUCUCUGGUGAAUGGCACCCUGAGCAGCUCCUCUCUGGGGUCCUCCUGCAAGGCAGUCAUGUUUGUCUUUGAACACACAGGCGCAGUAGGGUCUAUAUAACCUGACAUAUGCAGCCUAAAAAUCACCAGAGUUUGCUAAGCCAUGUGAUAAGAACCACAGGGCUUACGGGAAAAACAGGAUUAAAAACACAACACUUGAGGCCGGGCGCAGUGGCUCAUGCCUUCAAUCCCAGCACUUUGG